GCCCGCGGCUCGCGCGCUCCCGAGGAAGAGUGAGGGCGCGACGCGCACCAACGGUGGAGGUACGGGCGAGGCGGCCCCGCGGCGCCCAGCUUCUGCCGGUCCCAUGGCGCCCGCCGAAGAGUCUGCUUUUGGGCCCUGAGGAUCUAUUUUGGGGGCUCAGGCGCCCGCCCAGGAGUCUAUUUGUGGGAGCCGGGCGGGCCGCCGGGCGCCCCCGGGUCCUAGAGGCCUCCGAGGUGGACCAGGCUGGGGCUUGGGUCCCCCGCGGGCGCUGGGCCGGGACAGGGGGCUUGGGUCUCGUUGGGGCCGGGGCAUGGCGGGAGGUUUGGGCCUCACCAGGGCGCCGGGGCCUUGGACCGCUCUGCGUCCCAUGUUCUCUGUCCCCGGGCGCCGUCCUCCCCGCCCCCGCGGCCUGUGGCACUGGGCUUGCGUCUGUGGCUCUUGGGCGCAGCGCCCUGCCCGCUCUACUGCGGCGUCUGGCGCGGAGGCGUGGCUUGGCCGGGCCCGCCCACUUCGCGUCCGCGUCGUUCGGCUAGGGCCCCGUGGCUACCCGGUGCACGUGGACGGCGGGCUGCGUGGUUCCCGUGUCUUCACCCUUUCCCUAGUGACUGCGUUGUCGGCUUUACGUUUAUUCCUUUUUGUGGCCCGCUUUGUAAUUGGUGCAUUUUUUUCUAUGUAUUAUAACACAUGGCUCAUAAAAUAAAACUAAUUUCUAUUUUCAUCACUUCUUCAUAGACCACACUAUUCCUUUUGCUGUUUCUAAGUAAUUUAUUGGGGUCAGCAUUGUAACUUUAAAAAAUUUAAUAUCACUUAAUGUCCAUGAAAUUGCCAUUUAAGACUCCUUCAAUUUUUCUGACAUCUGGUAAUUUUCAGGCAAUGGAUACACUGAAAAGCAACUGUCUCAACAGCCCUACAGACAUUUAGCAAUUGAAGUUUCAGUUGCAUACAGUCUCUCUCUGGGUUAUCGUCAUUGCUUUGUCCAUCAGCCUUCUAGCAUUGGUAACUGUCAGAUCUUUAUUGCAGCCUGGGGUUCACUCUUGAGCUAAAGACUCAAAUAUGUCUGCAGCCAGGUCUUCCCUGGUUGCAGCUCCAGACAUCACCUCCGUGGAGGUCUUAUCAGCAUCUGUUUCCCACUUCCUCCACCCUAAGGAAGGACUCCAACUUUCCUAGGAUGGAGGAGUGGAAUUCCCUUUUUUUCCCUGGCGUUCAUGGGAGCCAUUGAUUAGGUUGGGACACUGUCUCCCUCCGCUUUCUAGGAGUUGGCUCUGUCUCUGGCCAAAAGUGAAGGCCACACUCCCGUGACUGCUCUGGGAAUGAGCUUGGUGUCUAAUAACCCAUGAAGGAGAGAGCACUUUGGAAGGCUCCUCUGUUCUCUCAUGGCCAUAAGGGGAAGCCAGCCUUGGGUGAAAGCAGAGGAGAUGGGAGAGCCAAGGUCCUUGAUGCCACUGUUGGGCCACUGAAAUGAAUCAAACAAAACCUGAAGUCCCUCCUCCUCCUGGACUGUUUCAUGAAUCAUCAUCACCCUUUACGGUUGGAGGAUGGUUGAGGUGGGUUUUCUGCUCCAAAGCCUGCUACUUGAACCAUCAUGCUCCCACUCCAUUGAGGUAAUGGAUUGGGAACCAAUUCAUCCUAAGUGUCUCUGCAUCUCAUUGCCACACUUAGUCUGGGCCAGCCUCUGUCUCCUGGACUUGGUGCUAGUCCCCCACAGUGUAACCAGAAUGUGCUUGCUAAGAACAGAGGGUUUCUACAUGUUGGUUCUGACUCCUUAGCAAGUUGUAAUUCACAACUAAUGUGGGUUGUGAAAUCAAUUCUGUGGGUCAUGAUCAGCAUUUUAGUUUUUAGAGAAAUAAUAGACUACAUGAAAAUAUUAGAGUGCAUGCAUGUAGUAUGCCGAACUUUUAAUGAAACAUUUUUCUGAGUGGUUUGUACUGGGUCGUGGUGUAAAAUGAGAUUUUAGAGAGAAGUGAACUCAACAGACAGGCACUGGCGUGUGGAGGCAGAGCCCCUAGAACCCCAGAAUCCUGGCCCAGCCUUAGUCCUUAGUCCCCGGAAAGCUAGCCAGUGGGGAGGGCCAGGGCAUCAGCUCUUCACACCCCCUGCCCUGUUCUCAGAGGCAGUCUGGGUUGAGAAAACGCAAGCCCUGCACCUCCAAGAGCCUCUCCCCUCUUUGCAGGAAGGCCCAGCUGUUUCCCACCAUGGUGCCUCUGUACAUCCCAGUCCAGUUCCUGAAAUGCGCUCUGUAGCCUGGAGAGCUCCUGCGCAUCCUGUGAAGCCCCAUCAAGAAUCCGCUCUCCUGCAGUCCUUCCCCGAGGCCCUCGGAGGGUCCAAGACAGCCAAUCCCUCUUCUCUGCGGUGACUCUUGCGGCCUCCCUCAUCUCGUUCCCUCCGCAGGCCUCGAGUUACCCUUGCGCCUUCCACAUUUACUGAAUGAACAAAGGCCGGGGCUGGAAUCAGGCAGGGCUUGAGCAAGUCGUGGCUCCACGUGCUAGGGAUGUUUCAGCAGCCCCUGAGAAGGAAGAGGAGGAAGCUGAGGGCCCGCUGAGGGCGCAGGACCUGAGGGAGUCCUACAUCCAGCUCGUCCAGGGUGUGCAGGAGUGGCAGGAUGGUUGCAUGUACCAGGGGGAGUUUGGGUUGAACAUGAAGCUUGGAUAUGGCAAAUUCUCUUGGCCCACAGGCGAGUCAUACCAUGGGCAGUUUUACCGGGACCACUGCCAUGGCCUGGGUACCUACAUGUGGCCAGAUGGCUCCAGUUUCACGGGCACAUUUUACCUCAGCCACCGAGAAGGCUACGGCACCAUGUACAUGAAGACACGGCUUUUCCAGGGGCUAUACAAAGCGGACCAGCGGUUUGGGCCAGGUGUCGAGACCUACCCCGAUGGCAGCCAGGACGUGGGGCUGUGGUUCCGAGAGCAGCUCAUCAAGCUGUGCACCCAGAUCCCCAGUGGCUUCUCCCUCCUCAGAUACCCUGAGUUCUCCAGCUUCAUCACCCACAGCCCUGCCAGGAUCAGCCUCUCAGAAGAGGAGAAAACGGAGUGGGGACUGCAGGAGGGACAGGAUCCCUUUUUCUAUGACUAUAAGCGGUUUCUUCUGAAUGACAACCUAACGCUGCCUCCAGAAAUGUAUGUCUACUCGACCAACAGUGACCACCUGCCCAUGACAAGCUCUUUCCGCAAAGAGCUGGACGCCCGCAUCUUCCUCAAUGAAAUUCCUCCGUUCGUUGAGGAUGGAGAACCAUGGUUCAUAAUCAAUGAGACCCCUUUGUUGGUCAAAAUCCAGAAGCAAACUUACAAGUUCAGGAACAAGCCAGCUCACACCAGCUGGAACAUGGGCGCCAUCCUGGAGGGGAAGCGCAGUGGCUUUGCACCCUGUGGGCCCAAAGAGCAACUUUCCAUGGAGAUGAUCCUAAAGGCUGAGGAAGGGAACCACGAAUGGAUUUGUAGGAUCCUGAAGGACAACUUUGCUAGUGCUGACGUGGCGGACGCAAAGGGCUACACUGUGCUUGCUGCGGCUGCUACUCACUGCCACAACGACAUUGUCAACCUUCUCCUGGACUGUGGGGCCGACGUGAACAAGUGCUCAGAUGAGGGUCUCACGGCACUCAGCAUGUGUUUCCUCCUCCACUACCCCGCCCAGUCCUUCAAGCCCAAUGUUGCUGAACGGACCAUACCUGAGCCCCAGGAACCUCCAAAAUUCCCAGUUGUUCCAAUCCUUUCAUCAUCAUUUAUGGACACAAACCUGGAGUCUCUGUACUAUGAGGUGAACGUGCCUUCCCAGGGUAGCUAUGAGCUGAGGCCACCGCCAGCACCACUGCUCCUGCCACGCGUCUCAGGCAGCCACGAGGGCGGCCACUUCCAGGACACCGGGCAGUGUGGGGGGUCCAUAGACCACAGGAGCAGCUCUCUGAAGGGGGACUCCCCGUUGGUGAAGGGCAGCCUUGGCCAUGUGGAAAGCGGGCUUGAGGACGUGUUGGGAAACACAGACCGGGGCAGUCUGUGCAGUGCUGAGACGAAAUUUGAGUCCAACGUGUGUGUGUGCGACUUCUCCAUCGAGCUCUCGCAGGCCAUGCUGGAGAGAAGCGCCCAGUCCCACAGCUUGCUGAAGAUGGCCUCGCCCUCACCGUGCACCAGCAGCUUCGACAAAGGGACCAUGCGGAGGAUGGCGCUGUCCAUGAUCGAGCGGAGGAAGCGCUGGCGGACCAUCAAGCUGCUGCUGCGCCGGGGCGCGGACCCCAACCUGUGCUGCGUGCCCAUGCAGGUCCUGUUCCUUGCUGUGAAGGCCGGGGACGUGGAUGGGGUGAGGCUGCUGCUGGAGCACGGGGCGAGGACCGACAUCUGCUUUCCGCCGCAGCUGAGCACCCUGACACCACUCCACAUCGCUGCCGCCCUUCCUGGGGAGGAGGGGGUACAGAUUGUGGAGCUGCUGUUGCAUGCCAUCACCGAUGUGGACGCCAAGGCAUCCGACGAGGACGACACUUACAAGCCCGGCAAGCUGGACCUGCUGCCCUCAAGUCUGAAGCUCAGCAAUGAGCCAGGCCCUCCCCAAGCCUACUACAGCACGGACACAGCCCUCCCGGAGGAGGGGGGCAGGACGGCUCUGCACAUGGCCUGCGAGCGGGAGGAUGACAACAAGUGUGCCAGGGACAUAGUCCGGCUCCUUCUAUCCCACGGAGCAAAUCCUAACCUGCUGUGGAGUGGCCACUCCCCGCUCUCCCUGUCCAUUGCCAGUGGGAAUGAGCUGGUUGUGAAGGAGCUCCUGACCCAGGGAGCUGACCCCAACCUGCCCCUGACCAAAGGCUUGGGCAGUGCCCUGUGUGUUGCCUGUGACCUGACCUACGAGCACCAGAGGAACAUGGACAGCAAGCUGGCCCUGAUUGACCGACUCAUCAGUCACGGGGCCGACAUCCUGAAGCCUGUAAUGCUCAGGCAGGGAGAAAAGGAGGCAGUGGGCACAGCCGUGGACUAUGGCUACUUCAGAUUCUUCCAGGACCGGAGGAUUGCCCGCUGCCCCUUCCACACGCUGAUGCCAGCAGAGCGCGAGACGUUCCUGGCGCGGAAGCGGCUCCUGGAGUACAUGGGCUUGCAGCUACGGCAGGCUGUCUUUGCCAAGGAGAGCCAGUGGGACCCCACGUGGCUGUACCUGUGCAAGAGAGCGGAGCUGAUCCCCAGCCACAGGAUGAAGAAGAAGGGCCCCAGCCUGCCCAGGGGCCUGGAUGUGAAGGAGCAGGGGCAAAUUCCCUUCUUCAAGUUCUGCUACCAGUGUGGCCGCUCCAUCGGGGUCCGCCUCUUGCCCUGCCCUCGCUGCUACGGGAUCCUGACCUGCAGCAAGUACUGCAAGACCAAGGCCUGGACCGAGUUCCACAAGAAGGACUGCGGGGACCUGGUGGCCAUCGUGACACAACUGGAGCAAGUUUCCAGGAGGAGAGAAGAAUUCCAGUGAAGCAGCAGCUGCACGUCCGAGGCUUGGGGAGGACCCAGGACUGUGUGGGUUUCUUACCUGCCUGAGCCACCUCAGGGAAUCUUCCAGCCUAAUGCAGGCAUUUCUGCACCUUUGGGGUCAUGCUUUGUAGCAGUGUCUCCCUUGCGACCUCGCAAUAAAUUGGCCCCACGGGGUGAUUUUGACAGUC